GCAGAGGCGGCGGCGCUGCUGGCCGGGCUGGGCCGCUCGUGCGCGGGGCUGUGACUCACCGGCCGGCGCCGCAGCCCCGCAAUCUGUUGAUAACUCGGUCCCAGCUCGGCCGCUGCCCUCGCGAAUGGAGAGCGGGUCCCCGGCGGGGGGAGCGCAGCGCGUCUGUCUCCGGGAGCGCGGCCCGGCCGCCCCGGCAGCCGCUUCGGCCACAGCAGAUGGGAGCAGCUCCCGGACUGCGCCCGCCCCGCCGCGGUCACCCUGAGGCCAGGGGCCCGGGAGCGCGACCUCCUGGCCGCCGUCUGGGACUUUGACCUUCCAGAGGCCAUGGAGGCUGGCGGGGAGCAGGGCGCCACCUGAUCGCCUCCCCCUGGACGCCUCCUCCAGCGGCGCUCACGCUUCCGCAACUUUGCAGCGCUCAUGGAUCUGAAGACAGUGCUCUCCCUGCCCCGCUACCCAGGGGAGUUCCUGCACCCCGUGGUGUACGCGUGCACGGCCGUCAUGCUGCUCUGCCUCCUGGCCUCCUUCGUCACCUACAUCGUGCACCAGAGCGCCAUCCGCAUCAGCCGCAAGGGCCGGCACACGCUCCUGAAUUUCUGCUUCCACGCGGCCCUGACCUUCACUGUGUUCGCCGGCGGCAUCAAUCGCACCAAGUACCCCAUCCUGUGCCAGGCGGUGGGCAUCGUGCUGCACUAUUCUACACUGUCCACCAUGCUGUGGAUAGGAGUGACCGCCAGGAACAUCUACAAGCAGGUGACCAAGAAGGCCCCUCUGUGCCUGGACACAGACCAGCCACCGUACCCCAGGCAGCCCCUGCUCAGGUUUUACCUCGUCAGCGGAGGGGUCCCCUUUAUCAUCUGUGGGGUCACGGCUGCCACGAACAUCAGGAAUUACGGGACAGAGGACGAGGACACGGCGUACUGCUGGAUGGCCUGGGAGCCCAGCCUGGGCGCCUUCUACGGCCCAGCCGCCAUCAUCACCCUGGUCACCUGUGUGUACUUCCUGGGCACCUACGUGCAGCUGCGGCGCCACCCAGGGCGCAGGUACGAGCUGCGCACACAGCCCGAGGAGCAGCGGCGGCUGGCGACACCCGAGGGCGGCCGUGGGAUCCGGCCAGGCACCCCACCCGCACACGAUGCCCCCGGCGCCUCCGUGCUGCAGAACGAGCACUCAUUCCAGGCACAGCUGCGCGCCGCCGCCUUCACGCUGUUCCUGUUCACGGCCACGUGGGCCUUCGGGGCGCUGGCGGUGUCACAGGGCCACUUCCUGGACAUGGUCUUCAGCUGCCUGUACGGCGCCUUCUGCGUGACCCUGGGACUCUUCGUGCUCAUCCACCACUGCGCCAAGCGUGAGGACGUGUGGCAGUGCUGGUGGGCAUGCUGCCCGCCCCGCAAGGACGCCCACCCCGCACUUGACGCCAACGGGGCCGCGCUGGGCCGCGCCGCCUGCCUGCACUCGCCGGGACUGGGCCAGCCACGGGGCUUCGCGCACCCACCGGGCCCCUGCAAGAUGACCAACCUGCAGGCCGCGCAGGGCCACGCCAGUUGCCUGUCACCGGCCACCCCGUGCUGCGCCAAGAUGCACUGCGAGCCACUGACGGCGGACGAGGCGCACGUGCACCUGCAGGAGGAGGGCGCCUUCGGGCACGACCCCCACCUGCACGGGUGCCUUCAGGGCAGAACUAAGCCGCCCUACUUUAGCCGGCACCCAGCAGAGGAGCCCGAGUACGCCUACCACAUCCCAUCCAGCCUGGAUGGCAGCCCCCGCAGCUCGCGCACAGACAGCCCCCCCAGCUCUCUGGAUGGCCCGGCGGGGACACACACGCUGGCCUGCUGCACCCAGGGCGACCCCUUCCCCAUGGUCACCCAGCCCGAGGGCAGUGAUGGGAGCCCUGCCCUCUACAGCUGCCCCACGCAGCCGGGCAGGGAGGCAGCGCUCGGGCCCGGCCACUUGGAGAUGCUGCGGAGGACACAGUCCCUGCCCUUUGGUGGCCCCAGCCAGAACGGGCUGCCCAAGGGUAAAUUGCUAGAAGGCCUGCCGUUUGGCACCGACGGGACCGGCAACAUCCGAACGGGACCCUGGAAAAACGAAACUACUGUGUAGAUGGGGGCAGAGGACACGGUGUUCCUGGAGGAGCUUCAGAGCAGAGUGGGGGGCCCAUCUGCCACAUGAGGUCACUGGGGGUACCGAAGUGACCCCGCCUUUCAGAAGCCGUUCACACCCCUGCCCCUUCCUUGUGAUCACACCCCUGCCCCUUCCUUGUGAUCACACCCCUGCCCCUUCCUUGUGAUCACACCCCUGCCCCUUCCUUGUGAAAGACCUCAGCGGGGAAACGCUCCGGGCCACGCCCACUCCCCUUAUCCCAAUUCCGCGUGCUGGUCCCGCACACGGUCAUCCGGUUUCUGUCCUGUGGUCUCCAGUCCUGGGGCACCCUAGAGGCAGAGCAGGGGAUUCCAUCAAAGGACCCACUGAGACCCCAGCAUGGCCCUGCCCGAGAUGCCCUGCUGCCCACGGAGUCCUGGCUUCCCCUGGUGUGGCCGGGCAGGGCCGAGAUCGCAGGAGGGGGCUGCCCUGACCUUUCCCAGUGUUCAAUGUGUGUGUCUUGCGUUCUACUCCGGGGGUGGCGGCGGCAGGUCUGUCCCCAGCAUUCUCGCUCUGGGCAGAACCCUCGGGACCCUCCGCUGUCGUGUGUCUGAGCCACCCCUGCAGCUUCACAGGGCCCCUGCACACCUCUGCCCACUCAGUGUGCCCUGUCAGCCCUGUCCUUGUCGUAGCCCCAGCCCUGCAGGGCUGAGAGCACCACAGAUGCUGGGGGCUGCUCUGGACUUUGGGGAUGGCUGUCAGCCUCAGAGGGCCAAUGGGGGGCUUUCACGGGCCCAAGGCUUGGGAAAAUGCCCAGACAUCCUUUAGUGAAGACUCGACUUCCAAAACCAGCCACCGCUGGGACUGGAUUCCACUCCAGUAUAGGCACUUAGCAACACGAAGGUUUAUUCCAAAAAGAAAAGGGGCUGACAGACGGGAGAUUCUCAUGGACAAAAUCCCUUUCCCUUUUUCUCGUCUCCAUGAACAUCUGGGUACCAAGCCCUGACUCAAAGGACAGAUGUGGAUGACAGCAAGACUUCUGUGAAAGCAAGUGGCCCGUCCCUAGGUGGGAGGGAGUCCAGAGGGUCAUGGGUGUGAAACUGUGCACAGCUUUCCCUCCCUCCCUCUUCCUCCUUGUCUGUGACACAUGUGCACCCACACACACACACACAAACACAUGUGCAUAUCACACACAUGCACACACACAAACACAUGUGCAUAUCACACACGCGCACACACCCAAACACGUGCAUAUCACACACAUGCACACACACAAACACGUGCAUAUCACACACAUGCACACAAACGUGCAUAUCACACACACGCACACACACCCAAACACGUGCAUAUCACACACACGCACACACACAAACACGUGCAUAUCACACACAAACACACGUGCACACAUACUUAACACACACUUGCACCUGCUGUGCACAUGUGCACACACACGUAGUAGUGUGUUUUCCAGCCACCCACACACUGGGUUUGCAUUGGAGAUUGUUUCACCCUGCAAACGUCAACGUCAGCAGACUCGUCGGUGCGCUGUGCUAUCCGGUUGGGAGGUCUCACCAGGAGCAGAGCCUCCCUAACGUGCACCUCCGAGAAGAGGGGUGUCGGGGAGUGUUCCCAGCACCUGCUCGGUGGAAGGGCUCUCCGGAGACUGGCACUCAGUAUCUGAGUAUGAGGAGCCUCACUUCCCGGGGUGUCGGUAAACUUGACCGUGACUCAGUAACCCACAGCGUGCUCCUCCCAGCAAACCCCGUGUGUCCUUACAGGUCGACCAGACGGGCCGUCGGAGGACCACCAGGUGGCUCUGCCUCUGCCUCACCUUCUCACCUGCUUCCAUAGCUGAUGUGAACCCGAAUCCCCACGCUGUGCUGUGUACGCACUGUAGGUGCAGAACCGUCCACACAAAAAUACAGUCUUGGCAUUGUUUGUUCUUUGUGAGGCUGGUUAAUAGCAUCCCCGUGUGUUUUUCUCACCCUCGAUGGGGUAGAGGGGCACCUGAAUGUGUGGCCCCCGUCUGUGUCCUGGAUCCUGGGGCAGGGCUGCUCUCCCUGGCCCCUGCAGCCCCUCAUGAACUUUCCACCCUCAGUGCCCCCGGCUGAGCAGAGAGGCGUCCCACCAUUCAACCAAAGAAAGUCAACAUUGAACAUUAAACCUCUGUGUGUUUCUAUACUGA